UGGGCAGGGCGCCAAAUAACAUCCUGUGCGCUGCUGAGCUGAGCUGGGGCGCGGCCGCCUGUCUGCACAGACAGCACCAUGUCGCUCAUGGUCGUCAGCAUGGCGUGUGUUGGGUUCUUCUUGCUGCAGGGGGCCUGGCCACAUGAGGGAGUCCACAGAAAACCUUCCCUCCUGGCCCACCCAGGUCCCCUGGUGAAAUCAGAAGAGACAGUCAUCCUGCAAUGUUGGUCAGAUGUCAGGUUUGAGCACUUCCUUCUGCACAGAGAGGGGAAGUAUAAGGACACUUUGCACCUCAUUGGAGAGCACCAUGAUGGGGUCUCCAAGGCCAACUUCUCCAUCGGUCCCAUGAUGCAAGACCUUGCAGGGACCUACAGAUGCUACGGUUCUGUUACUCACUCCCCCUAUCAGUUGUCAGCUCCCAGUGACCCUCUGGACAUCGUCAUCACAGGUCUAUAUGAGAAACCUUCUCUCUCAGCCCAGCCGGGCCCCACGGUUUUGGCAGGAGAGAGCGUGACCUUGUCCUGCAGCUCCCGGAGCUCCUAUGACAUGUACCAUCUAUCCAGGGAGGGGGAGGCCCAUGAACGUAGGUUCUCUGCAGGGCCCAAGGUCAACGGAACAUUCCAGGCCGACUUUCCUCUGGGCCCUGCCACCCACGGAGGAACCUACAGAUGCUUCGGCUCUUUCCGUGACUCUCCCUAUGAGUGGUCAAACUCGAGUGACCCACUGCUUGUUUCUGUCACAGGAAACCCUUCAAAUAGUUGGCCUUCACCCACUGAACCAAGCUCCAAAACCGGUAACCCCAGACACCUGCAUGUUCUGAUUGGGACCUCAGUGGUCAAAAUCCCUUUCACCAUCCUCCUCUUCUUUCUCCUUCAUCGCUGGUGCUCCAACAAAAAAAAUGCUGCUGUAAUGGACCAAGAGCCUGCAGGGAACAGAACAGUGAACAGCGAGGAUUCUGAUGAACAAGACCAUCAGGAGGUGUCAUACGCAUAAUUGGAUCACUGUGUUUUCACACAGAGAGAAAUCACUCGCCCUUCUGAGAGGCCCAAGACACCCCCAACAGAUACCAGCAUGUACAUAGAACUUCCAAAUGCUGAGCCCAGAUCCAAAGUUGUCUUCUGUCCACGAGCACCACAGUCAGGCCUUGAGGGGAUCUUCUAGGGAGACAACAGCCCUGUCUCAAAACCGGGUUGCCAGCUCCCAUGUACCAGCAGCUGGAAUCUGAA